AGAAGCUGUCUAUCGGGCUCCAGCGGUCAUGUCCGGCAGAGGAAAGGGCGGAAAAGGCUUAGGCAAAGGGGGCGCUAAGCGCCACCGCAAGGUCUUGAGAGACAACAUUCAGGGCAUCACCAAGCCUGCCAUUCGGCGUCUAGCUCGGCGUGGCGGCGUUAAGCGGAUCUCUGGCCUCAUUUACGAGGAGACCCGCGGUGUGCUGAAGGUGUUCCUGGAGAAUGUGAUUCGGGACGCAGUCACCUACACCGAGCACGCCAAGCGCAAGACCGUCACAGCCAUGGAUGUGGUGUACGCGCUCAAGCGCCAGGGGCGCACCCUGUACGGCUUCGGAGGCUAGGCCGCCGCUCCAGCUUUGCACGUUUCGAUCCCAAAGGCCCUUUUUAGGGCCGACCACUUGCUCAUCUGAGGAGUUGGACACUUGACUGCGUAAAGUGCAACAGUAACGAUGUUGGAAGGUAACUUUGGCAGUGGGGCGACAAUCGGAUCUGAAGUUAACGGAAAGCUACCGCGGCCCAUAGCGCUCACAGCCGUAAAGACUUAAGUCGUUGACCGAAAGCGGCUUUUUCACUUACCUGGGCUUUUUUUUUUUUUUUUUUUUUUUUUAAAGCCUUUAUCGGUAUGAAAGGUUGAAUGCUCUAGGUUUGAGCACUGCUUUCUCGGCUUGCUCUUCUGGUGCAGUAUAGGCACACCUAGAGGGCCACGUCAGUCUUUGCGAUCACCAAAUCUGGUUCUGAGAAAUAGGCACUGGCAAUUUACACAUGCCUUGCUGUGUAAUCUCACUAUAUUUGCUCAGGCAAAGUGGGAGAAGCAGCCUUAGGUUUUCAUUCUAGAGAUGCCGGCUUUCCCACCUGAUCGGCUUAGAGUUCACGAUUGACUGUUUUGGGCUUCAUUUCACCCUCUACAUAACAAGCGGGUGGACUAGAUGCCUUAGCAAGGGUCCGUGUUGUGUGGUGUCUCCAGCCACGCACUCAGCUCAAUCUUAGCACAGUUAAAAAAUGCCUUUCUAGCAAGUUAUCUGCCCAGUGCCUGAAAAGUAUCAUUUCUUGUGUUCAAUAAAAAGCCUCCUAAUUUAAUCAAGGACCUAUGAGAUAACUGUCUUUUAGUUGUGGCAUUGCAAGGAUACAAAUGCAGAGAUAUUUUAAAGUGAUCCUUCUGUAAGAGUGAACCAACGAUAUGAUCUGAAAGCAACUUCACAGGUAAUUCAGGCUUAUGAUUUUACUGUGUAUGUAUUUGGGAGAAGAAAUUCUGUCAGCUCCCAAAGGAUAAACCAGCAGUUGCUUUAUUGGUCUUCAGAUGUGGCUGCAAACACUUGAGACUGAACUAAGCUUAAAACACGGUACUUAGCAAUCGGGUUGCCAGCAAAGCACUGGAUGCAAGCCUUGCCUUCCAGAAGCUUACCAGUCGGGUUGCCAGCAAAGCAGUGGAUGCAAGACUUGCCCUCCAGGAGCUUACCAUCACAACGAAGAAGACAAAUAAAUGCAUAAUAUAUAGACGACAUAAAUCCAUACUGUACACAUUUAAGAAUAAACAGUCCAGUAGUAAGAGGCAGUACAUAUUCAAUCUGCUGAGAAAUGUAGACAAUAACUACUAUAAGAAUCCUAAUGCUACAGAAGUCACUGGCUGCUGGGAAACCGGGGAAAACUUGGCUAUGGACGUGGGGGCUUGUGUCGGACUCUGAAUAAAGAGCAGAAUGAUUGGCGUCCUACUGAGAUACAUAGUAAAGGGGGCGAGGGCAGGGAGGAAGUGGCAAGAAUAACAUUUGUGAAGAUGUCCAGAUCGCUGCAGUGAAUGCUUUUAACCUGUCAACUGUGAUGAAACAAACAGAAAACCGAAGCCCUGGCUUCUUCUGAGGUGCAAAUAAAUGACCGAGAAGGUGUUAUCUAAGACCUCUACAGCCAUUUGUAUCUGGCCGUGUGUAGAGUGGGCUCUGCAAGACCCUGCCUCACUUUCCCACUAAGAGGCCUUGGACUUCCCAGCUCCCAGAGACUGUAGAGAUCACCUCUGUGGCCUCCUGUCACGAUUUCCUAAGGCGAAGAGCUUCAUUUGCCCAACGGAGGCCCACGUUCUUCCUGUCUGAUCUACUGUCUUCCCAAGGAUCUGAACUCGGGCACCAGCGUCUGCCCACAUGUCCGACGAAAACAACGUAAAGGAACUACUGAGUCUGGACAGAAAAUCCAGACAUACCAUGCAGCUUCUAAGAGGACCGAGUGCCUUCACUGGAAUAGUGAAUCUCCUUCUGUGGACAUGGACAGGGAACGGCUCGAUAAAGCCCAGAUUCACAAAAUUCCGCCCACACCCCGUGCCCCCGGGAAUUUUGGCUUAGGGGCAGGAUAUGGGGGUUACCACUGUGCUAGUGGAGGUGGCGCGGGGACUGAACGGCAGCCCCAGCGCAGUUCUCCCCACGUUUGUCCGCAGAACCCCGGCGAGGCCGAGGUGGUCAUUUCCCUCCCUAGCCGGAUGGCCGCGCCGGGUGAGGCCGGUUUGGGCGCGAAGCACGGGCGUGUGGCGCUCCACUUCCGCAAAGGCCAGCCGCGCUCAGGACCGCGAGCCCUGAGCGUCCCCCUAGUGACCCCUGGCCUCGUGCCCGACGCCCCGUCUCUCCUGCCCCGGCCCCCCCGCCACGCAGGGCCCCGGUCACGCGCGGGGGGAGCCGGACCGCCAAAGCCCGCGAGCCGGCGCCCAGGAAAGCGUCCGCAGCCCGGCCAGUGCGGAUAGGCCAAUUGGCCGAAGUCGGCAAAGCUCAAGACGGCACCGCAGCAGGGGGACCCGACCCCGUUUUGUUGGGAGCCUAAGCGGAAGUGCCUUCCCCGCUCUAAUGCCGGAGGAGCACGGAGGGCAAGCGGUACAGCUUCUUCCAAGUGCUGAUGUGGGUGGCUCUGAAAAGAGCCUUUUGGAUACGAUGGAACCUCCGGCCGAACCGCCACUUCUUAAGCCCGCUCUCCACGGAUGCGGCGGGCCAGCUGGAUGUCCUUGGGCAUAAUGGUCACGCGCUUGGCGUGGAUGGCGCACAGGUUCGUGUCUUCGAACAGCCCCACCAGGUAGGCCUCGCUGGCCUCCUGCAGCGCCAUCACGGCCGAGCUCUGGAAGCGCAGGUCCGUCUUAAAGUCCUGCGCGAUCUCGCGUACCAGCCGCUGGAAGGGCAGCUUGCGGAUCAGCAGCUCCGUGGACUUCUGGUAGCGCCGGAUCUCCCGCAGGGCUACGGUGCCGGGCCGGUAGCGGUGCGGCUUCUUCACCCCGCCCGUGGCCGGCGCGCUCUUGCGGGCCGCCUUGGUGGCCAGCUGCUUCCUCGGGGCCUUGCCGCCGGUCGACUUGCGAGCAGUCUGCUUAGUACGGGCCAUAGCGAACCAAAACACAGGCUUACCAGCGCAGCGGCGGGGAGAAAAACGAGCUCCUAGCCCCGCCGCAGCCGUCUUUAUAAGCACAGUCUUUUCCCGAUUGGGCGGAACAAUAAUUGAAAAUCCCGCGCUGGCUGUCCAUUGGCUGUGACGUCACCCGUCCUAAAGUCACCGGUUGGCUUGGGCAGAUUCCUCCCUAAUCCCGCCCACCCCGCCUCACUUUCUACUUACCAGUUGGCGAAGUUUCGCAAGCUUGUUUUUCCCCUUUCCUUCAGGGUGAAAGUCAUUUUCCAUUGCAGCUUUGUCAGAUUGUUCCCUUUCCGCCCUUCGCUUCCUUAGAACACACUGCCCGCAAUACCCCCCCUUUCUUGCUGCGCCCUACAGCUCCCGCGUGGAACCUCAUUCUUCCAUUUGCCCCCCGCCCCCAGUUGCUACUUGGCGGAUCGUUUUUCGCCUGUCGGGUGCCUUUUGGGUGGGAGAGGUGCCCGCCCCCAGGACGCAAGAUUCCGCCUCCGAGGCCCUUACUCUCCGCCGCCAGGGCGCUUUGGAAAACAAAACAGAAACUAAGACUUAAGUCAGCUCAGUGAAGCCAAGACCCAGCUCCGCCACACUAGCGAGCACUACCCGCUCAGGGCCCUCCCCAUCGGGGGUGGGGACGAGGAGCACGUCCCGCUGGUGCCAGACUAGGUCUAAGUGUCCGGCCAUAGCCUGCGGAAACCACUAGGGAAGCGCGCGCUCCGCGCGCAACACUUCAGCGCGUUGGGUACUGCCCGCGGCGCUGGUGUUUGUGACUGUGUGGAGCGGACCGUGGCGGCGCCCAGGACGUUUGGUGCCUGCACCUGCCCUGGGAAGUCCUAGGACUGGGGACCCACUCAUCGAAGAGCCAAGGCAGUUACGUGCUCCAGAUGGAAGACGGCGCGCACACACACACACCCCGCCCCGCCCCGCCCCGUCCCGUCCCGUCCCGUCCCGUCCCGUCCCGUCAGCUCCAGGUUCGCUAUUCACUACUGAGGAACGCUGGACUGAGAGUGGCCAGCAUUAACAACUCUUUUAUUUGAAAACGUGGGUGGCUCUGAAAAGAGCCUUUUGAGUUCACAGGUGCCCCUUCGAGACGCGGGCCGGGCUGGGCCCACUUGGGCCGGACGUCAGCCUCACUUGCCCUUUGCCUUGUGGUGACUCUCCGUCUUCUUAGGGAGCAGUACGGCCUGGAUGUUAGGCAAGACGCCGCCCUGGGCGAUGGUGACUUUGCCCAGCAGCUUGUUCAGUUCCUCGUCGUUGCGGAUGGCCAGCUGGAGGUGACGAGGGAUGAUGCGCGUCUUCUUGUUGUCCCGAGCCGCGUUGCCCGCCAGCUCCAGGAUCUCGGCGGUCAGAUACUCGAGGACCGCAGCCAUGUAGACGGGCGCGCCGGCCCCCACUCGCUCCGCGUAGUUGCCUUUGCGCAGCAAGCGAUGCACUCGCCCUACCGGGAACUGAAGGCCAGCGCGGGACGAGCGCGACUUGGCCUUGGCGCGGGCCUUGCCUCCUUGCUUGCCACGACCAGACAUGACAGCGAUAGUAGUCACCGAGAGAAACUCCUGCCUGGCGAUCGGGAAAGUCGCCGAAAACGCCGCUGCUUCACCUUUUUAUAGACAGAACGGCGAUUGUCCACGGAGCACUUUGAUUGGCUCAAGCAAAUUUUGUCCCGAUAGCCAAUAGGAUAGCUCAGCCAGAAUCCACUCAUUUACAUAAUCUCGUCUCCCUCGCAUUGCGCGCCGCGGAAAACUCGCGAACCAUAACGCAGCGUCAUGCGCACAGCCUCUGUAAGUACACAGUCGUUUCCGGUAGACCCCGAGCCUACCGCUCUGCUUGCGUUCUCGGGGGUCGGUGUCGGUCUUGGGUCUGGCCAUGCCUGAGCCUGCAAAGUUCGCGCCGGCUCCCAAGAAGGGCUCCAAGAAAGCCGUCACCAAAGCCCAGAAGAAAGACGGCAAGAAGCGCAAGCGCAGCCGCAAGGAGAGCUACUCCAUCUACGUGUACAAGGUGCUGAAGCGGGUCCACCCCGACACCGGCAUCUGGUGCAAGGCCAUGGGCAUCAUGAACUCCUUCCUCAACGACAUCUUCGAGCGCAUCGCGGGAGAGGCGUCCCGCCUGGCGCACUACAACAAGCGCUCCACCAUCACGUCCCGGAGAUCCAGACGGCCGUGCGCCUGCUGCUGCCCGGCGAGCUGGCCAAGCACGCCGUGUCCGAGGGCACCAAGGCGGUCACCAAGUACGCCAGCUCCAAGUGAGUCCCUGCCGGGACCUGGCGCUCGCUCGCUCCCUCCCUCCCUCCCUCCGCGGGUCGCCGGCUGCUUUGUCUCCAAAGGCUCUUUUCAGGGCCAUUUAACCACCUCAGUUAAAGAAUCUUUCUUGUGUUGUCAGUCCCAGUUGAUGUUUUUGGCUUCACGUCUGGUUAACUUUAGGAGAGCACACAACACCAAGCACAGAUAACUAUUUUCUUUUCACAUAGGCAUUGCUAUAAGUAAGCUUACAUAGAUUGAUAGUGGUAUCUUACUAUGGCAUAGAUAGGUUGGGGCUUGCCUUAGAGGGCUGCUCUUGAACUGUCUUUGGCCUGGUUACGUACCCGUGAAUAUGUGCCCAGGAGAUUGUUUCCUGUUGAGAAACGCAGUGUUAAUUUUGAUAAGUUUAUGUAAGAUCAAAUUGUGUAUAUGAACAAAGGUUGGGUCCGCUCUUCAGUGGUAAAAUGAAGGUAGAGAUUAAAUGCAUUGUAUGCUCUCAGAUGUGUACUUAAAAGGGAAUAGCUCAACUUUUAUAUAUGGUAUCGAGAAACCUGAGGUUUUUAUAUCAUUGGUUCACAAACACGUGCCUACACCACCACUCAUGUGAAAAUUCCUUAAGGAGGUAGAUGGAAGUUCGAUUUUGAUAACCAGGAGUUAACACCGAUAACCUUCUGCGCUUUCUAGUUGAGAUACCCUAAAAUCUACCCAAUACCAUUAAAUGGUUUUUUUCCCCAAGAGUUAUCACUCGGAAAAGCUUGUCCAGUUUAAGGGUUUGUUCCAUACAAUAGCAACAAAAUAUACGAUUUCUGAAGCCAGAGUUUGGGAUCCCUGAAGAGGAGAAGGACCACCAAUUUGCAAGGGAGGUUGAUUAGGUUUGUUUUCUGCUUUGGGAACACUGGACUUGGAAUCACACAGCCUCAUUAACCUCAAAAUAUUAUACUGAUUGCUCUGGGGAUCGUAAAUCCUAGGCUGGCCACAAUAGAAGCGAGGAAAGCAAUUAGGAGGCUGUUGCAGUGUUGUGGGCUGGAACAGUGAUUAAGACUUAAAGUCUCUCCAGACCAGCAGCAUCAGCAUUACUUGAAGUUACUAAAAAUGAAAAUUCCCAGGUUCCAUUAUUUGUGUUAAGCUUUCUGGGUGAUGGUGAUAUAUGCUAAAGUGUGAAAAACAACGGAUAAAUGACAUGCUGGAGUGCAAUGGUGGUAAUGGAAACAAAUGUUGGAUUUUAUCUUUGAGGUAGAAUUAAUAGGUGUGGCUGAGGAACAGGAUUUAGCUAACAGUGAAACCCCUAGAUUUUUGGCUUGAGCAACUGUGUAGAUAGUGGUACUAUUAGGAUAGAACACUGAGAGAAGAUAUUCGUUGGGACACUGAAGGGAGAUCCAGAGUUCCGACUGAAAUUUGAGAAGCUCUUUGCUAUUCAAGUGGAUAUGUGCAGUUGACAGUUUGAGAGAUGCAUCUAGGGUUCAGUAAAGACAACACAAGCCUGUCUUUAGGGUCUACCUGUGAACUGUGAACACAGCAAUGAGAAUGAUGGACAUCACCUUUAAGUAUUUUUCUAGACUUUAUUACUCAUGUGUUUGUCAUGAGGUGUAACUUAGUAGUUCAUAGUCCUAUAAUGUAUGUUAUUGACUAGGUAGCAUUUAUUUUUCUAAUUGUUUCUGUUAUAGUGCUGCCACAUGUGUUUCCCAGAAACGCAUUUUACCCACAGUUCUUAGGGUUGGCCUGAUUAGUUUAAUUGCUGUCUGAACCUGCUUCUUACUGUGAUUAGUUCAGGAAUCUAGAUCAAACUCAUUGGCAUUUAACAUUUCAGGAAGUGAACUGAGUAACAACUAACUCAGCAGGGGAGUGUAGUAUGCUAUUAUCUUUUGGGAAAGCAGCUUAUUUGCUUUCAAGAGGCAGCAGGAGGAUGGACUGUCUUUAGGUAUGAAGGCAAGAAUGAUUAUAGACAAUAUGCAGAGGAGGACACAGUGUGGGAGAAUCAGGGAACUGAGCCACUCAUGGAGUUCAGCCAACCUUGGAUCCCUGCUGCACCUUUGGACUUCCAGUUAAGCCAAUUUGUCUGACAUAUUUACUUAUACCAGUUUGAAUCUUGAAAUAUUUCAGGAAUAAUAAUUUCCUAGAUAAAAGGAAAGACCUUUCAUGAAAGGUCUCAAGUCAAAUAGGGUCAAUUAGGACAGAGUUGCUCCAAUUACAUAUUUGGAACAGAUGUCCAAAUGUUAAUACUUGACUAAGGCUAAAGACUAAUAUUACCAUCACAGGAAAAAUGUCCAGGGUUUUUUUUCAGAUGUGAAAUUUUAUUUAAAAAUUUUAAAUAAACUAAAUCAAAAAAUUUUAGUAGUUGUACUAAUUUCCUGGGGCUGUCAAAGUACCACAAACUGUAUGGCGUAAAACAACACAAAGUUAUUCUUUCAUGGUUUUAGAGGCUAGAAGUUUGAAAUCAACGUGUUGGUAGGGCCAUGCUCUCUCCAAACCCACUAGGGGAAGACUCCUGUCUUUCAGUGUCUGGUAGCCCCACUUGUUCUUUGGUUUCUGGCAGCAUAACUGUAAUCUCUACCUCAGUUUUUUCAUGUAUGUCUCCAUGUUUUUUUACUUUCUUUCUUGAGAUGGAGUUUCACUCUUGUUGCCCAGGCUGGAGUGCAGUGGCAUGAUCUUGGCUUACUGCAACCUCUGUGCCCCGGGUUCAAGCAAUUUUCCUGCCUCAGCCUCCCGAGUAGCUGGGAUUACAGGCAUGCGUCAGCACGCCCGGCUGAUUUUGUAUUUUUGGUAGAGAUGGAGUUUCAUCAUGUUAGUCAGGCUGGCCUCGAACUGACCUCAGGUGAUCCACCUGCCUUGGCCUCCCAAAGUGCUGGGAUUACAGAUGUGAGCCACUGCACCCGGCUGUCUCCAUGUCUUCUUAUAAGGGUAUCAGUCAUACUGGAUUAGGGCCCACCCUAAAGACCUCAUUUUAACUUGAUUACCUCUGUAAAGACCCUGUUUCCAAAGAAGGCAAAAUUCUAAGCAACUAGGGGUUAGACUUCAACAUAUCUUUCGGGGGGACACAACUCAACCCAUAACAGUAGUCAAUGGCUGUGGCAGGCUAAAUGUGGCUCCCAAAUAUGUCCAUAUCCUAAUCCCUACAGCCUGUGAAUAUUACCUUAUAUAGCCAAGAGGAUUUUGCAGAUGUGAUUCUGAGAUUGAGAGAUUAUGCCAGAUUAUCCAGGUAGGCCCCAAAUGUAAUCACCACAGUCCUUAUAGGAGAGGCAAGAAAGUCAAGUGUAGAAGGAGGCGAUAGAAGGAGAGAGGGAUUUGAAGAUUAAUAGGCUGCUUGCUUUGAAGACAGAGGGAAGGGACCAUAAACCAGAAAUAAACCUCUAGAAGCUGGAAAAGGCAUGGAAAUAGACCCUCCCUUAAGGUCUCUGGAGGGAGUGCAGCCUUGAUUUCUACCGAGUAAAAUUGAUUUUGUACUUCAGACCUCCAAAACUGUAAGAGAAUGACUGUUGUUUUAAAACCAUUGAGUUUGUAGUAAUUUGUUGCAGCAGCCACAAGAAACUAAUACAACAUCUAUAUAGAAUUUUUUCAAUAAUUGGAGAAAUUUGAAUAUGGAUUGCAUAUUAAUAUUACUGAAUCAGCAUUAAAUUUGUUAGGUGUAAUAAUGUGAUUGUAGCUAUUUAGGAGAAUAUCCUAUUUUUAAGAGACAUGCCACCAUAUUUAGGGAGAAGUGCCAACAUAUUUGCAGUUUAUUUUCAAAUGGUUCAGAGGCUGUCUGUGUACAUGAGAAGACAAAGAUAAGGCAAAUGCAGCAAAAUUGUAAUAAUUGGUGAAUCCAGGUGAAGGGACUAUGGCUGGUCUUUGUACUUUUUUUUCCAACUUUUCUGUAGGUUUAAAAUUUUCAAAAUAAAAAAAUGGGAAAUACUUUAAAAAUUGUAAUCAAAGACAUUAGUACAGAAACUUUCAUAAUGUAUUUUAUUUUUACAGUAAAAUUAAUUUAUGUAAAUUGAUAGAAUUUUACUAAUUUCACUCCCAAGUUACAUUAAAAGGCUUACAUAUGUUUGAUAAUAGCAUAUGUAAACUAGAACUCUGAAUGAUAUCCAUUGGUCAUAAUACGUACUAUGUAGCGGUAAUGGUGACUUUUGUGAUUGCACAAGUCUAGAGAUGCCCCAAAUGACAUUGACUUAGACAUCUGGUUAUUCUAAGGCUGAAACUGAAGUUGAAUAGAAGGUUUUAGUCAAAUACUGAGAUGAAAACUGAGGCAGUCCUGGCGGGGGGGAGUGAGUGUGUGUGUAUAUAUACACACAUAGACAUCAUGCUUCUAAACAUUUACAGAAAGAAAGGGUAGAUUAUCUACAAAAAAAUAAGAAUCAGACUGAUAUGAGAUCUUACAAACCUAACCCCCUUCUCUUUCCUAAACUCCAGAUUCUCAUAUUUCUGACUUCCUAUUUGAUAUUUACACUUCGAUAUUUACCAGGAGUCUUCAACAUUUUGUUCAAAACAGUACUCUUGGUUUUCUUCCUCCAAGACUACUCCUUACUCAUAUCAGCAAAUAGCAGCUCUUUUCAAGUGCUCAGUGUAAAAACCUACAAUUAAUCCUUGAUUUCUCUUUCAGUCAGCCUAUACUAAAUCAAUUUCAUUUAAAAUAUCUCGGCUACUACUCUGCAUCUCCACUGCUACCAUCGGCCUCUCCAGUCACAUUCUCCAAGAGCACUCUAUCUCAUUUAAAAGACAAAAUCUCUGCAGUGGCCUGUGAUGCUCCUUAAUGGCCUACAUAAUCCAGCCCUCAAGCACCUCCGUGAUCUCUGUAAAACUUUCCCUUGGUCACUGUGCUUCAGCCACAUUAACCAGCUUGCAUAUUUCUCACAUUCACCAAGCUUGUUCCUGCCUUGGGGCCUUUGUACUUACCAUGUUCUGUUCUGAGAAUACUCUGCCUCAAGAUAUCCUACAACUAUCUUACUGUAUUCAGCUCUCUGCUCAAGUAUUAACUGAUGAAACCUGUCAUCCCUACUCCACUCCAUGUUCUGCUUUACUUAACAGCAAUUGCACAUAUGGCCCCCUGAAUAAUAUACAUUUAGUCACUUAUUUUUACUUAUCUGCUAAUUAAAAUGUAGACUUUUUCUAUUCUGUUUACUGCUGUAUUCCCAGCAUGUUUUAUCCGAAUGUGCAGUGGUUUCUUUUCUUCUCCCUUAUCGUGGGAAGUGAUGUGCACAAAUACACAUAAUGGAGCCUGAAUGUCAUAUUGCUUUCAUACCUGUGUGAAUUUUGGUAAGAAAGGAAAAGUAGCGAUUGACAGGUAAUAUAAUUACAUUAAGUCACUCUCAUAGUUAGCUGUUUAUUGCUUUCCUGCUCUUAUUCUCAGUCCCCAGGACCAAAUGUUGACCACUACCUUCCCCCACAUAUAAUUAGGUUAUUUACCGAACGCCAUGCAGGUGGCUGUUAAAAGGAAGAUAUAUACUUACCUUAUAAACUCAACUUUUCCCUGUUGUCUUUCUGUCUCACCCCUACCUCCAUGCUUUAAAUUAACUUUUCAGGCUUAGGCCUUAUCUCUCAGUAGAGCCAUAUAAGGUAUGUGUAAAAGCAGGAAAAUGUUUCCUGGGGAUGAAGCUUUGAAAAGCUUUUUUUUUUUUUUCUUUUGGCAAUAAAAUAAGGUAGAUUCAGCACAAUACCUAAUAACUAAAAAAUCUGUUUUUAAUUGGGUGGGGCAGACAGCAAGUGUGUCAUCCUGGAAGAUACUAUUUGGGAUUUUAUGUAGGUACAUAAGAGAAAAAAGUGAACAAAAGCAAGGGGCUACCAGGACGCCGCAGUAUGCUUAACAUGUAUUUUCUAAGUUUGUAUUAUGCCUUUAUCUUGGUACUUUUAUCUUCUGUUCUCACUUGAUCUUUUUGAAAUGUAUUUUAAAUCCUAAUAAAAAUAUAUAAAGUCUGGAAUUAAUAAAGGAUUAAAUGAAA